CCGCAGUCGCCUGUCGGAAAUGGCUGCCGGCCGGCAGGGGGAGCGGCGGAUCAGGCGCGGCCUGGAAGGCGGGCGGCCGGCAGCCAGAACGGCUUCUGGGACGCCGACUUUCGCGCAGGCGGCGGCGGCGGCGGCGGCGGGUCCCUGAGCUGGAAGCCGUUUGGGCUGCUCGGGACCCGCCUCCACCUUUUUUUGGACGCUCGGCUGCAGCUGUUGGGCUUCCUCUGCUCCCUGAAGCCCUCCACCCUCUGUGACCCGCGGCGUUUCUCUGGCUGCUGGCCCGGAGCAUCUUCUGUCGGCGGAGGCGCAGCUCCGGACUACCCCCACCCCUUCCCGAGCACACCUUCCCACAUCUGCCCCCCGCUUCUACACGCAGUCGCCUGCUGCCCUCCCCGCUGGCUCUUUUUGCCGGGCUCGCCUCCUUUCAGGAGCCACAGUCAGAGGAGCCGCUUCCUGUCCGAGGGUCCAGGUGCUGCAGGACCCUGGCUCCCAGGCCCAGCUCCCCUAGAGCCGGCCUCGCGCUGCACGGGCUGGACCGGACAGGGGUGCGCGGGGCGUGUGUGCGCGGCGGAGCUCCGAGCCCAGCGACGGGGACAGCACCUAUUCCGAGCCCCUCGGAGGCGAGCCAGGGCUGCCCGGCUGCUGAUGGGUGCUGCUUUCUCUUCCCCACAUUGAGCGAGAGCUUCGGCUCCUUUUAUUAAUAAAAUCUGUUUGGCUCUCAGAAGACUUAAAUUUUGUGGAUUUUGCCCCUCCCCCGCCACCCGCACCACCCCACCCCCGCCCUUCCCCGCAACCUGGAUUUUUCUUCCCUUUUUAAAAACUCUAAAAGCUUCAUCAAGUCCUCUUGGUUCGACUCCUUUGGUGGAGGAGGAAGCGCAGAACACCACAACAUGUCCAUUAUUUCCCCCAUAUGUGAUUUACUUAAGAGUCGUCUUUAGCAUUUCUUGUCACUUUGUCCUAUUCUUUGUCCAAUUUAGGUAGCUUCAUUUUUACUGGCAGAGCUCCCCGUGCUUUCUUUUGUUUUUAAAGGCUUUGUGUGUUGCAGCCAUGCAGACUCUGCAGUUUUCUGUAUUUUGUUCGGCAGUGAGUCCUGCAUUCUGAUACAGUGACUAUCGCUGUGACCUGUGUGCUGGGAUAGUAACUGCGGGGCACAGAGUCUGGAGCGAAGCGAAGCCUUCUCAGCGACUUGCUAUUUAGCAGAGGGACUUUGAAAUAUUUUGUGAUGAAAGAAAAACCGUUUUCUUAAACUGUUAUUUGAUGUGUUAAAAAUACCUUAUCCUGUGGGAAUUUCCCAUUCGUUUGCUUGUGGGGAGCCGGAGGAAUCAUAAGAACUCACGAGCAAGAGAGAAUCGAGCCUAAGUGCUUUCUGGAAGAGUCAGAAUUGUGGCUCUUCAGACUUCCGGAAACGUGCUUAAUGUCCAGAGAUGUGAGGGGCAUACCUACCUAAAAAAUGAUUGACAGGCGUAUGUCUGUAUCCCUCCACUUCUCGCUUUUCUAGUGGGGGAAAACCCUGUUAAUACUUGGUGUGUAGUUGGGAUCUUUCAGUGAUUAGGCCUCAAGAGUUUUGACCUCGGAGUAAAAAGAUUUUAAGGGAACAGUUUGGAGAGAAGUAAGUCGGGCCAGGCCGAGCAUGGGAAAUGUAUUUCUAGGAGAGAGGGCAAGUCCAGAGGGUGGUUUGAAGCCAGCAGAAGACUAGAGAGAGACCUGUUCUUUUCCGCAGGGCCCUAGGCCAGCUGUGGAUUGGAGGGUUAUGGGUGAUGAGGGGCUGCAGGAGUGAUGCGGAGUCCUUGUCUCAGUUGAGACUGGUGGUCUUCUGGAGGAGGGUGGGAGGGAUUCCCUGAUGUAGACUCAGGUGUUAGGAGAAAAAUGAAGUCCCAUCAGACCUACUCUUGGUAAAGGUUCGAGCGCCUUUGUAUGUUACUCUAGAGUGAGGCGAGGAAUAUGAAACCAGGACGUUUCAUAACGUCCUAAAACUGCCUACUCCAUUCGCUGGUUAUUAAGUUUAGCUCAGAAAACUUCUAUUAACAUAUUUCUAUUUUAUUUUUGUUACCCCUUCAUUUCGGCAACUAUCAUUUCGAAGACUUUCAAUGAUAGGGCAGCUGACUGAGAGGGAAGAAAGGAUUUUUCACGUUUGGAGGUUUCAUGGAAAUAGCAUAGCCCAGGCAGAGAGAGUUUGUGAGCUCAAGAGGGACAGAGGUGGGCUCACCUGUAAGCUUCAUCUUUUCUUUUCUUGCCUGAACCAGUUGCACAGUCCUUUUAAAUUUUCAGUCAUUCAGACCUCUUGGGUGAUGUUACUAGGGAGAAGAGAAGCAGGAUUUAAAAAACCUGUGAUCUUGAAAAUAGAAGAGGAUUGGGGAGACUCAUUACUAACAUACUUCCCUCUCCCACAGUUAGGCCAUAAAGUGCAGUGUAGGAUACUACUCACAUGCACCCAAAUGACCCAUCAAAAGUCUAGAAGUGGAGCCAUAGGAAGAUGAACUGUAGAAUCUGUUGGAGAGUGAAAGCAUCAUAUACAUAAUAUAUAAGAAUGCCUACUAUACGCAGCCAUACAAACGGAAUCCAUAACUGAAUGAGCAAAGCUGUAUUCCAGUGAAACUUUAUCUACAAAAGCAGGCAGCUGCCGCUUGCGGGUGCCUGCCUUAGAGUGCCACCCCUCACACACAUGCCUUUCCUUUGGUAUAUUCCUUCAUUUGGCUGUGUCCAAUACCUUUUGGACUGGUCAAUAAUAUUAAUGGUUAACGUCCUGGAUGUUUGCUUUUUUGACCAUUUUCCCUUUAAAGUCUCUUUUCCAACUUGCUUUUAAAUGUUUUUUCAGCAAUUUUGACCUACUCUUUCCAGCAUGGCUUCUUUUCUUUUUCUUUUUUUUUUCAAUUUUUCUAUUGAGACGGCGUCUCGCUCUUUUCGCCCAGGCUAGAGUGCAAUGGCAUGAUCUCAGGUGACUGCAAACUUCCGCCUCCCAGGUUCAAGUAAUUCUCCUGCCUCAACCUCCCAAGUAGCUGGCAUUACAGGUGUGUGCCACCACACCCGGCUAAUUUUGUAUUUUCAGUAGAGACUGGGUUUCACCAAGUUGGCCAGGCUGGUCUUGAACUUCCACCCACCUCAGCCUCCCAAAGUGCUGGGAUAUAGGCUUGAGCCGCCGCAUCCGGCUUCCUUUGUUUCUGAAGUAGAGCUGUAAAAUAUAAAAGCACAGUGGCUUCGAAUGGAGAAAAUAGUUGAUGGGAUCCCAAAUUAUUAAUGGAGUCUGUGGAAAAUUAAGGGGGGCCUUAAAGCCUUAUGCCUGAAAUCUUGGAGGUGAAACGAGAAGGAGGUCUUGGGAAUGGCCUUGCUGCCUUGAGUAGGUAGGGUGGUGAAAUUUUCCCCACAGCAAAACAUGUUUUUGUGCUUCCUGGGAGCAAGGCAAUUGUCAGUGAGGGCCUAGAGUCUAAAAGGAUCUUUGAGGUCAUCCGGUCUAACCCCUUAAUUUACGAGUUAACAAAGGACAAGGAGCUUAUGAGUCAAGAACGAGGAAUUGGGAAGUUAGGGGACCUGAUGAAUCAGAAAUAUGGUAAUGAUGAUGGGAUGGUAAAGCGUCUCAAGCUGAAUUCACCCACAAAGGGUGAAGGAGAAUGCCCGAGUCAUAAGCUGAUUUAAGGCUGGGCACGGUGGCUCACACCUGUAAUCCCAGCACUUUGGGAGGCGGAGGUGAGAGGAUCACCUUGAGUCCAGGAGUUCAAGACCAGCUUGAGCAACAUUAUAGUAAGACCCUGUCUCUUAAAAAAAAAAAAAAAGGAAAAACCUGAUUUAUGUAUGGCUUAGCAAACUUGCUUCACUUUCUCUAUCUCAUUCAGGGAGGCCCAGGGCACUAACGAUAUCAAUUGUAUGCCUCCACAGCAUAAAAUAAAAAUCAUGUAUGUUUGAGAAGCGAAAACCGUUAGAUUAGUUUAUAUUCUAGGCACUUGCAUACUAAGUUGACUGUUCUGAGAAUAAGUUAGCAAAAUCCAUCUGAAGACCUUAUUUGAAAACCUUGUUUCUACAUCGCUACCCAGCCCUUAUGAAAAUGACGCAUCUCAUUUUAGGAGGGAGAGUGAGAAAGAUAGGAAGAAUGCAGAAAUCACCUAUAAUUUCACAAUCUAGAAGUGCCUCUGUUGGUGUUUUUGCUUCUGUUUGUUUUUCUAUUCAGAAAUAUAUACAUAUGCAUUUUAAACAUGUUAUACUGCAUAUAUGGCUUUGAAUCUGUAUUUUUCCAGCUAACAUUGUGAACAUGUUUUCAUUUUAUUUAAAACCAUUGAAAAGCUUCCUAAUGGUAUCAUAGUCAUAUCAGUGACAGUCACACUUUGUUUAACCUUGCUCCUAGUCUUGGACAUUUAAUUUAUAUAUUUUAUACAGAUGAUAAAGAAUAAUGAGGUGAUUGCAUCUUUACAUACAAAUCUUGCUCACCUAAAAUAUAUUCCUAGAAAGUGAAAUUGCUGAAUCAGAGAUAAGAAAAUUUUGAAGGUUUUUUUCUUACAAAUGGCAAAUUACUUUUCAGUUUACCUUUCUACUAACACAAGAGUACCUGCCACAUUGUAGCAGCCAGCAUAGUUCAGAGUUGUACUGUACUUUAAUCACUAUUUUAAUGUUUUAGUAUGAGCAUUUUGGAAGUUAAAUCUUUUUUCUCACUCAUGAUUCUUUAAGAAUAAUUUCUCGGAUAGAAUUACAGGGAAAGAGGAUAGACACAGUUUCAGUGUUUUUAUUACUGCCAAAUUGUGCUCCAGAAAGGUGUGCCAAUUUGCAAUCCCAGCAGCCAAGUGUGGGAAUGUUUACCCUGGAUCCUGCUUAGCACCAGAUAUUAUAAUUUUACAAUACUUUGAUGAUUUAUUAGUGGAAAAUAUCACAGUAUCUUGUUUGAAAUGUGUAUUUCUUUGAUCGCUAGGAAGGUUAAACAUAUAAACAUGUUUAUCACUUGAACCCUUUUUUUGUGUAACUUCUUAUUUAUGUCCGUUGACCACUGUUGAUUGCUUUCUUUUAAUUCUGUCAUAUUGAGCAGGCUUCCCCAUUUUUAAUCAAAUUUAAGCUUUUUUUUUUUCCUUCUGAAUACAUAGAAUCAUUUGAUUCUUAUAUAGUCAAACCUGUUGAACAUUUCUGGAUUUUACUUUUGCUUGGAUUCCUGGAAAAGUGGCUGUACUUGAGAUGAGAUUACAUGUAUAUUUUCCUUUUCUUGUUACGGUUCAUUUAUUAUAAUUAACUCUUGAAUCCACCUGGAACUUAUUUUUGGAUUUGGUUUGUCAUGCAGUAAUCUGACUUUAUUUUUUUUCCCAAAUAGAUGUGUCACAUUAUUUAUUGAAAAAUGUAAUGAGGUGUUCUUUAAAAAGAUUGCAACAAGGUAAUAUUUUUAAUUACAAAAGUAAUACAUAAUGAUUGUAAAAUGAAUUAAGACAAAAUGAAUCCUCUAAGUAAACAAAUGGUAGAUAAGCAAGAAGCAGUAUACAGGGCUGUAGGUCAUACGGACCUGGAUUUGUAACUUGGUUGCUGUAUUGCCUUGAACAAGUUUCCUAUCCUUGGUGAUACACCACUGCUUCAUCGGUGAAGUGGAAAUGACAGUACUCCCAUGUGGCUGAUGAAAUGUAUGUGUGAAGUGUGUUAUCUAGAGUACUGUGCCUAGCACACUGUAAAUAUAAAUCAGUAGCAAUUAUGAAAAAGCCCUCUCCUCCCCAUCUUCCAAGGGUAUGUGGUGCAUUGAAGUGCGGACUUUCUGCGUUAGCUAAGGGAUAGUGCUGUUUGUCUUCCUUAGCUGUCUAUGUUGAUUGAGCUGCCAUCAAUCUGAAUCUCCAUUACUAUCAAUUCUUCAUUAGACCAAUAGUUUUGGAGUUAGGGUUGUGUGCUCUGCAUUAAAAUCACCUGGGAACUUUGUCAAACUGCAGGAGUUUUCCCCCACACCUAGGAAUUCUGAUUUAGUUAAUGUAGCACGGUCCCGGUUUGUUAUUUGAAAAAAUUCUUAAGUGGUGAAUCUGAUUUUUACACAUAAUUAAACUGACUGGUAAAACAAUACGAUUUGGAUUUGUGGGACAUUAGCGAACUGGUGGGAAGGGAAGCAGAUAAGGCAAUGGCAUAAUUUUCAAAUUGAGGACUUAUCCUGGGAGUUGAGACUUCUGGGCCCAGGUUUGUUGCCAAGUAAACAGAUAACUUGGAGUAAUCAAUAGCCUCAUUUUCCUUGUUAAUAUCUAUAUAUUCAGCAGCGGAAGGAAUGCUCACCACUUAUUGAUGAGUUCCUUUUGUAUUUUGUGAUUUGUCUGCUAGUGGCAUUUGUGGAACACCUUGGGAUUUAGAAACCUACUCUUAAGCCCAAAGAAUAAAUUGUUUUCCCUUUCAAACAGCCCUGUAAUAAGGGCGGCUCAAACUCUGGUUCUCUGGUUGCAUCAUAAUCUUCACUCUUCAGUCAGUAGGUCAAGGCACAACCAGUUUUUCACACUUCGUUUUGCUUUUUAAUUGCUGAGGAUGUUCUGUUUCCCUUUUUUCAUCCAGGCUAGGUUACACAGUAAGAAACCACUGUGGUCGUUGGAUUGUGAAAAACAUAGGGCCUUGGUCUCCUGUAACUUGGGAAGUGUCUACAUGUAGUUCUUAGAGCUUACUCUUUAUCUACAAUUAGUUUCCCUGGGAAGUGCCUUUUUUUUUUUUUUUUUUUUAAACAGAAGACAAAUCAGUGAUAGUGUUGGGAAAUGUGUUUUAGUGCUUAUUAACAUACUUCCUGACUUCACGAACUAGGUACUGUCUUGCCUUGACAGGCUGUUUGUCAUGCCUGUAGUUAGGAAAUCAGGAAAUGAUGUUUUUUUGGGUUGUUAGUACUUAAAAACAAAACAAUCCUCUGAAAUACUGCUUUCAGUGACCUCACUGAAAUGGUUUCCUGUGGAGAACUCUCUUUACCUAAUUGGAAGGGCUCCUGGUGAUGGCAGCAAUGACAGCAGCAUGCAGACAGCUCUGUAGAACCCGCACCUGGGUUGUCAUGGAGUUCUGCCACUUGAUGGGCCUAUUUUGACCUAAAUGAAAAAGAGAAAAUAGUACUACAAGCACAGAUAUACAGGUGGGCCAUAGGCACAGUGGCAAACAUCUUUUGUUCUGAGUCUGCUAUUCUCUUUAGCAGGUAAAUACUUUGAAUAUAGUGUUGGUUUUGGGUUUUAGAGGAAUAUUAUGUGUGUCAAUUGUAAUUAUUAUUCAUGGUUACAGCGGAGUAGCAGUGAUAUGGAGAAUGUAAAAAUGAUACACAUGAUAGGCAUGUGUGUGUGUGCCUGCUCGCACUCUUACUUGAAUUAAUAUAGACAGUGUAACAUAAUAAAGGCAUUAAAGGUAUGAGCUUUACAGCCAGCUUGCUUUGGUUUGAAUUCAAGUUUUACCACAUAACAUGGGUGACCCAUGGCUCAUUAGCCUCUGUGCUUUGGUUUCCUCGUGUACAGAACAGGAAUAACAGUAAACCCACUUCACGGGAUUGCUGUGAGGAUUAAGUGAGUGUGUUGAGGAAUAUAUGGUAAUAGGUUUAACCCGGCAUACAGUAAGCAUUCAAUACCUGUUAGCUAUUAUCAUAAUUAUUUAAGAUAUUAGAGGCCGUUGAAGGUUUCAUUGGGAACAUCUGGAAAGCGUCUAGCCUCUCUCUCUGUUUCUCACUCUGUUCUCCCUUCAUACCUUCCACGUGGAAGGCAUAACAGCCAGAUGGAGCAGUGACUCCCUUCUUCCCUGUCGCGCCUCCUGUCUCUCCUGUCUCUCCGGGUGAGUGUUUUAGUGUAGUUUAACUUUUUUUCUUUCUUUUGGAGUAGUCUGAUAAUUUUCUGCAUAUAAAAAAAUUUACAGUUUUAUUAAAAGAUGCAAAAGAAGACCUAAAUAGAGACAUAUCCCAGAUCCGCAAUGGGAAGUUUCAAUAUCAGUGUUUUAGUUUUACAAGGAGAAAAGUCGAGUCUGUAGGAUGGUUGUUAUAUCAACAAACUCUUGAAAGCAAGGCCGUGAGUAAUGUUCCUGCAGAUAAUCGCAGUUUGCUAUUGUGAUAAGGGAUGUGAGAGGAGGAGGGCCCUGGUACGUGGAGGUGGAGGGGCGAGAAGGUGAAGGGGAACACCAGCACGUGCACAGUUCUGGAUUGGAACUCUGAGCCCCGACUUCUCAGCCCACCGCUCAGACUCUCGAAUGGAGUGAUUACAUUACAGCUUUCCAGGGCUACUGCUUGGUUCAGCCCUCCAAUGAGGAGCUAGCAGAUGGCGACUUCUGCUUUGCAUUUGUCAGCAAAAAUGUCUGAUUAGGGAAAAGAGUAAAAGGUAGAAUGCUGGCCACAAUCUGAAUGAUAAAUCUCUGUAUACAACUAUUUUAAUUUUUUUUCCCCUGGGAGAAGACACUGUCAUGAUCCUGUUCUAGUCAUAGAAGAUGUGCUUGCUGCCAUUGAACGUCUGAGGUGUAGAUGUCUGUGUUGCUGACCACUGGAAAAAGGAUUAUCAGGAGGGAGGUGAAGAUGGGAAAAGUAAAUUUGAGAGUCAGCCAAUCAGGGGGCUAAGCGAAGCUCAUUGGCAAGCUCUGGGAGGUGAAGGCAGAAAAGAGGUUGAGGACAAGCCUGCAGGAACAGCUACAUUUGGGGAGUGGUGAAAAGGGGUCAGAGAAAGAGAAGCAGGAGAGGACAUGGGCAGGAAGUGUAAAAUGCAGACUGACUUAAUAUGAGGUGCACAGCAUGGGUGAGAACGCAAGACACUUUGAUAGGAGAAAUGAAGGUGUAAGUGGGGAGAAUUUUUAUGCUUCUGGAUAGGAUUACCCUAAUAUUGUGUUAAGUAUUUUUAUGUCUAUAUUCAUGAGAGAUUUUUUUUUUGUAGUUUUCUUUCUUUCUUUUUUUUUUUUUUUUUGAGGCAAGGUCUUGCUCUGUCACCCAGGUGUGAUCUCACCUCCCACCUCAGCCUCUAGUAGCUGGGACCAUGCCUGGCUAAUUUAAAUUUUUUUUUUUUUGGUAGAGAUGGGGUCUCACUGUGUUGCCAGGGCUGGUCUCAAGUCAUCCUCUCCCCUCAGCCUUCUGGAGUGGUGUGAUUACAGGCAUGAGCCGCAGCGCCUGGCUUGUGGUAUUCUUUAUUUUGGUACUGUCUUUGUCUGGCUUUAGUCAGGGCAAUGCUAGGUUUAUAAAAUGAACUGGGAAGUGUUCCUUCCUCUGGAAGAGACAGUGUAGAGUAGGUGUUUAUUUUUCUUUAAAUGUUCAGUAGAAUUCUUCAGUGAACCAUCUGGGGCUGGAGAUUUCUUUUUUGGGAUUUUCAAAAGUAUGAAGUCAGUUUACUUAAUAGUUAUAAAACUAAUUCAGAUUAUUCCCUAUUGGAUGAGUUGUGGUACUUUGUGUUUUCCAAGGAGUUGGUCUAUUUCACUGAAGUGUAUAGAGUUGUUUGUAGCCUGCAGGGACUGUGGUGAUAGCCCCUGUUUCAUUCCUGCUAUUGGAAAUUUGUGUCUUUUCCCUUUUUUCUUUGUCAUUCUUGUAGGUUUUUCAAACCAGUGACAAACCUCUUUGUUUUCUUGAUUUUUCUCUUCUGCUUUUCUGUUUUCGAUUUCGUUGAUUUCUGCUCUUUAGGUUUGUUUUGUUUUUUUUCUGGGUUCUUGAAGGAGGAGCAUAGGUUAUUGAUUCGAGACUUUUCUUCAAUGCAAGAAUUUAUGCAUAAAUUUUCCUCUUAGCACUGUUUUAGCCAUGUUCCCAUUUUUUUUUCUUCCAUCUAUAAUAUCUUACUUAAUUUGUGCAAUAACCCUGGCGGUAGGUAGAGAUUUUCAGACUCACUUUACAAAGGAGGAAAUGAGCUCAGGGAGAUUAUGUAACAUUCCCAAAUUCUCAAGGCUGAGCUGCAUCCUGAGCCGGGUAGUCUAGCUGCAGGUCCAUAUGGCCAUCCAGCUGCCUCCUGGCUCUGAAGUUCUCUCUCUGUAGUUUAUAAUGUAUUCAAUACAAUAUAUUAUUUGUUAAUGGAUUCAUUAACAUUAUGUUGAGAGCCAUGGGGAACACUUUCAGUAUGAGGUAGGAGGACUGGGUCCCAGCAAAGCAGAAAGGGAGGAUGAGUCAGGGAAGUAGAUGGAACACUAAAAAAGCACAGCUUCAUGGAAGUCCAGGGGAGAAUUGAGAGUUUGUAGGAUGAGGAAGUGAUCAGUGAUAGGAUUCAUUUAUUUAACAAAUAUUUAUAGAGUGUUUACAGUGUGCUGGACACUGGGCUGGGUGCUGGCCACGCAGCAGUGAUCCAAACACAAAGGGUUCCUCCCCUCGAGGAUUAGGCUUUGGUGGGGAAGGGAGGGAAUUAAUAAAUUACAAGAUAUUAGGAAGUAAAUCAGUGGGUCGGUGCCAGAGAGCAUCGGGGGGUAAGAAAGGCAACUUUAAAUGGUAAUGCCAGGAAAGUUGAGGCCUGAAGGAUGAGAAAGAGUCUGCCAGGCAGAAGCCUGGGGAAGAACAUUUCAGACAAAACAGGCAUAAAGUUUUGAGAGCGAGAAGCUUGGCACAGUCGAGGAGGAGAGCAAGCCCUGGAGGUUCACUCUUUCAAGAAGUCGUGUGCUGAGGUGUAAUGCUACACAAGUCAGAGGAAGGAAGGGUCCUGAAACACAUGGCCUGAUUGUUGGCAAAGGCAUCAUAAGAAGCUGGCAUUUAUUUCUGUUCUAACCUAUUACUGUAUAACUGUGAAUAGACACUAUGCAUAUUUGUUGGUCAGCAAAACCAAGAAACAAGAGCUAUGGCAUUUGAAAAAGUCUGUCUGAUUCCAGGGUGUUUUUCCUGGGUUUCAUCAUCAGGUACCUCCUCCCUUUCAUCUCAGCAAGAAUGUGGCACCUUUUAUCGUUUGAUAAAGAUUAAGGACAUGUUCUUUGGUCAACAGCCAGAACUUAAAAUCUGCUGGAAUAGGGUCAGAGACCAUUUCAGCUGCAGCUGAGGAAAAUGAAAUGUUCAUUUUAUUUGGUGCCUUGUCUGGGGAGCACACUAACUCUUCUGGAAACGUGUCAGUGAAACAGAGAUCGUUUUGUGGAAUAGCAACCCAUGGUUAUGGCGAGUGACCCGACGUGAUCUGGGGGGCAGGCUGCAGAGGACUCAUGACAGGCUAUACCAUGCUGCGGAAUGGGGGCGCGGGGAACGGAGGUCAGACCUGCAUGCUGCGCUGGUCCAACCGCAUCCGCCUCACGUGGCUCAGCUUCACGCUCUUUGUCAUCCUGGUCUUCUUCCCGCUCAUCGCCCACUAUUACCUCACCACUCUGGAUGAGGCUGAUGAGGCAGGCAAGCGGAUUUUUGGUCCCCGGGUGGGGAACGAGCUGUGCGAGGUGAAGCACGUGCUGGAUCUGUGCCGCAUCCGGGAGUCGGUGAGUGAAGAGCUCCUGCAGCUGGAGGCCAAGCGCCAAGAGCUGAACAGCGAGAUCGCCAAGCUGAAUCUGAAGAUCGAAGCCUGUAAGAAGAGCAUUGAGAACGCCAAGCAGGACCUGCUCCAGCUCAAGAAUGUCAUCAGCCAGACCGAGCAUUCCUACAAGGAGCUCAUGGCCCAGAACCAGCCCAAGCUGUCCCUGCCCAUCCGACUGCUCCCAGAGAAGGACGAUGCCGGCCUCCCUCCCCCGAAGGCCACUCGGGGCUGCCGGCUACACAACUGCUUUGAUUAUUCUCGUUGCCCUCUCACCUCUGGCUUCCCGGUCUACGUCUAUGACAGUGACCAGUUUGUCUUUGGCAGCUACCUGGAUCCCUUGGUCAAGCAGGCUUUUCAGGCGACAGCACGAGCUAACGUUUAUGUUACAGAAAAUGCAGACAUCGCCUGCCUUUACGUGAUACUAGUGGGAGAGAUGCAGGAGCCGGUGGUGCUGCGGCCUGCUGAGCUGGAGAAGCAGUUGUAUUCCCUGCCACACUGGCGGACGGAUGGACACAACCAUGUCAUCAUCAAUCUGUCACGUAAGUCAGAUACACAGAACCUUCUCUAUAACGUCAGUACUGGCCGUGCCAUGGUGGCCCAGUCCACCUUCUACACUGUCCAGUACAGACCUGGCUUUGACUUGGUCGUAUCACCGCUGGUCCAUGCCAUGUCUGAGCCCAACUUCAUGGAAAUCCCACCACAGGUGCCGGUGAAGCGGAAAUAUCUCUUCACCUUCCAGGGCGAGAAGAUUGAGUCUCUGAGGUCUAGCCUUCAGGAGGCCCGCUCCUUCGAAGAGGAAAUGGAGGGCGACCCUCCCGCCGACUACGAUGACCGGAUCAUUGCCACCCUGAAGGCGGUGCAGGACAGCAAGCUGGAUCAGGUCCUGGUGGAAUUCACCUGCAAAAACCAGCCCAAACCCAGCCUGCCGACUGAGUGGGCACUGUGUGGAGAGCGGGAGGACCGCUUGGAAUUGCUGAAGCUCUCCACCUUCGCCCUCAUCAUUACCCCCGGGGACCCUCGCUUGGUUAUUUCCUCUGGGUGUGCAACACGGCUCUUCGAAGCCCUGGAAGUCGGUGCCGUCCCGGUGGUGCUGGGGGAGCAGGUCCAGCUUCCCUACCAGGACAUGCUGCAGUGGAACGAGGCGGCCCUGGUGGUGCCAAAGCCUCGUGUUACCGAGGUUCAUUUCCUGCUCAGAAGCCUCUCCGAUAGUGACCUCCUGGCUAUGAGGCGGCAAGGCCGCUUUCUCUGGGAGACUUACUUCUCCACUGCUGACAGUAUUUUUAAUACCGUGCUGGCUAUGAUUAGGACUCGCAUCCAGAUCCCAGCCGCUCCCAUCCGGGAAGAGGCGGCAGCUGAGAUCCCCCACCGUUCAGGCAAGGCGGCUGGAACUGACCCCAACAUGGCUGACAACGGGGACCUGGACCUGGGGCCAGUGGAGACGGAGCCGCCCUACGCCUCACCCAGAUACCUCCGCAAUUUCACUCUGACUGUCACUGACUUUUACCGCAGCUGGAACUGUGCUCCAGGGCCUUUCCAUCUUUUCCCCCACACUCCCUUUGACCCUGUGUUGCCCUCAGAGGCCAAAUUCUUGGGCUCAGGGACUGGCUUUCGGCCUAUUGGUGGUGGAGCUGGGGGUUCUGGCAAGGAAUUUCAGGCAGCGCUUGGAGGCAAUGUUCCCCGAGAGCAGUUCACGGUGGUGAUGUUGACUUAUGAGCGGGAGGAAGUGCUUAUGAACUCUUUAGAGAGGCUGAAUGGCCUCCCUUACCUGAACAAGGUCGUGGUGGUGUGGAAUUCUCCCAAGCUGCCAUCAGAGGACCUUCUGUGGCCUGACAUUGGCGUCCCCAUCAUGGUGGUCCGUACUGAGAAGAACAGUUUGAACAACCGAUUCUUACCCUGGAAUGAAAUUGAGACAGAGGCCAUCCUGUCCAUUGAUGACGAUGCUCACCUCCGCCAUGACGAAAUCAUGUUUGGGUUCCGGGUGUGGAGAGAAGCUCGGGACCGCAUCGUGGGCUUCCCUGGCCGUUACCACGCAUGGGACAUCCCCCAUCAGUCCUGGCUCUACAACUCCAACUACUCCUGUGAGCUGUCCAUGGUGCUGACAGGUGCUGCCUUCUUUCACAAGUAUUAUGCCUACCUGUAUUCUUAUGUGAUGCCCCAGGCCAUCCGGGACAUGGUGGAUGAAUACAUCAACUGUGAGGACAUUGCCAUGAACUUCCUUGUCUCCCACAUCACUCGGAAGCCCCCCAUCAAGGUGACCUCACGGUGGACAUUCCGAUGCCCAGGAUGCCCUCAGGCCCUGUCUCAUGAUGACUCCCACUUCCACGAGCGGCACAAGUGCAUCAACUUCUUCGUGAAGGUGUACGGCUACAUGCCCCUCCUGUACACGCAGUUCAGGGUGGAUUCUGUGCUCUUCAAGACACGCCUGCCCCAUGACAAGACCAAGUGCUUCAAGUUCAUCUAGGGGCAGCGCACGGUCUGGGGAAGAGGAUGAGCAGAGGGAGGAAGAUGGCUCCCAAGGUUCCUAGGCAUUGCAGGACCUUGGGCACAUCUGCUGGUGGGUGGCCCAGAGCCUCUGCUGGAAGGGGCAGCAGGAGGAGUGGAAGGAAACCGCUGCCUUUAUCUUGAAGUCAGCCACACUGGGCCUGGAGCCCUGGGCGGAGUCCCCGGGGUUCCCCACACAGGGCACUGACUGAUAGCUUACACUGAGGACUGUGGCGACUCUGCAGAGUCACUCACACCGUUCGUACGCCCAGGACAGCUGGUUCGUGGUUUUUACAUUCAAUAACAACUAUUAUGAUUAUUUAAAAAGAGAAAGUUUCAGAUUUGCCAUUCAAGGCUUAUUUAUAUAUAUGUGUGUGUAUAUAAAUACAUGCACACACUUGCAUACAUAUAUAUUUUUGGCUGGGGGAGUGUGAGUUUUGCCUUUCUAAGGGAGGGACCGCGCAGGCUCCUUUGUUCUGUAUUCUGGCGGAGAUGGGUCCUGGCCUUGUGUCACUGGCUUAUCCUUAAAGAUCAUCUCCCAUCCUCCCCAGCGCCAUCUGUGUGCAGCAACCAGAAAGGGAUGAACUUGGCCCUCUUGCGGGCCUGGACAAGGUCUCUUCCUUACCCUUUCUGUUGCCAGUCAGCAACCUGUAACUCACAUUCUCUUCCCAGUGAAUCCCUGGGAGCGCCUGACCCUGGUGGGCUGUUCAGCUUCCUGCUGCUGGGGCCAGCGAUUUUUGAGGAUUUAUCUUUAGGCCAGGCUUGCCUCCGUACUUAUCCCUGCUCUCCCAUUUCUCUCUUGUUUGAGAGAGAAUGAGGAAGCAAAGAGUGAGAAAGAAUAGGGGCUGAAGACGCCACUCCCAGAUGGCUCUUUCUAUCCUGCUCUUCUGUUGAAACACACGUGCUGUGGGCCUCAGGCGUUUCUGAAGUGCUCUUUCUUGGAUUGGACAGGAGAUCAGCAGCGUGCACAUCUGCUGUGGUCUGAAGUGGUUUGCAGGUCAGCCUCCUCUCCCUAGUGUAGAGCAAGCCAGUGUCCUUCGAGGAACCCACCCGGCUGGCCGGGAAGUUUUACAGCAAGGCGCCUGCCUUGGGAUAAUUCCUUGGUGAAAUUCACCUUCCCCCCGCCUCUGUCUGGAGCCCCAUCCUGUGUUAUCUGUGGUUUUUGGACCCCUAAUGUCAGCUUGGCUGUAGGACUCCCCGAGGUUUGGUAUGUGCUAGAACAAUGGGAGGCUGUGAUUUGCUGUGUAAGCUCACAUCCAGCCUUGGAAUCUAACGGGCAUUCACAACCCGAGUUACCACUUUCCACUCCCUGCUUAGGAUUCUGUUCCCUGGGCUGAAACUGAAAUAAGCUAAUUUUUUGGGUCACGGUGGCAGUAGGGGAACCUAGGAGGGUGUGAGUGGCAUUUGUCAGGGAUUUAGCCCAUGACGUGUUUCUUGAACCCUACUUUCUGGAAGUGGAGUUGACUCUGGAAGUUUUCUAGCAACUGAACAAAAGCUCAGGUUUGUCCUGGUCAUGCACAUGCCUUAAGCCAGUUCCGUCUUCCCUAGACCUUGGCAUCCUGUGCUUCUAUUUCUUGGAAUACGUUCUCCUCUGACCUGCCUGUACCACGUGGGUCCUCUUCAAGUACUGUUUUGAAGCUGGGCUCUUUUGUGUAGCUCCCACCCACCUGUAGGGCUAGCUCGGCUUAAGGGAACUCUCCCCAUUGGCAAACCGGACCCGGCCGCCGCCAGGACUGUGUUUCCAAAGGUUCCCCGCCCCCAACCCCAGCAUCAGCCUGUAGCUCCCCUGCUGAGGCAGUGUGGUUAUGUUCCCAGCAGUGGGGGUCAGACGCCCUUCCUCAGAACUUUCUAGUUGCCCUCUACCUGACUCCUGACUUGUAUUCCUUUUAGCAGUAGCCUUCUUCCCUCGGGGAGCCAAAGAGUGUGGUGUGUGGCGCUAUAUUGUGGCUGCUAUUUCAUCUGGUUUCUUUUAAUGUGAGGAACUCACAUACUGACUUCAGUGGGACUCGGUGAGCCGGGGCCGUCUGUGUGGUGGGACCCCCUUUAGCGGGACUCAGUGAGCUGGGGCCGUCUGUGUGGUGGAGCCAGGGCCUCUCCCUUUAGUGGAGCCAGGUUGUCGGGCCCCGAAUGUCACUGGUGGAUCUAAGAAGGGCUGAGUGGUCUGACACCAAAACAUGCCGCAGGGAGGGCUGUGGUGCCGGUGCUUCCAACAAGGACAGCCCUCCUUGACCCUGAAAGGAACACUGGCUUGAAGGACUGCAGACAGGCUCUGAGGGGCACGCCCUCCUCAGCGAGAGGCAGCAAGGUGGCCACAGUGUCACUGGUCAGGUGCUUCUCACCACGGGAAAGCCGCCGACCUGUGACUCGCUUGAGAUGGGAAAGCGGCGCCACAGACCCCGGGUCUCCUUGGCUGUCUGUGGGCCGCCCCUGGCCACCUUGUCCUGGCUCGCAGGGUGCAGGAGCGCCUCGUUCUCUGGGUGGCCGGCUUGCUGCUCCGGUUUGGGCUGUCUUACCAUAACACCGUCCCAGGGCUCUGCAGGCCACUGUGAGCGCUGGCUCCCUGGGCAGUGCUCCUCCGUGUGGACUGUGCCUCAGGCCAGGGCUCACCAGCUGGGGUCCUGUCCGGAAGGAUGGGAUCUUUCUGGGAGCUGCGCCGGACAGAGUGGGGAGCUCCUAGUUUGUGGGGGGAAGCUUUGAUAUCCAUGCCACGUCCAUCCACCCCACCCCUUUUCGUCACGAGCACAAUGGUCUUACAUUGGAUUUUUGUAAAAAAAUAAAAAUAAAUGGAGACUUUAACUCAAGCAGCUUGGAGGUCUUUUGUGGUUUUCCUCAGCAAGUAUGGAAGAGUGACCUGAGAGAAGGCACCUGCUUGAUUGCUUGAUUCCAGGUCGCCACCUGUGUAUGCCAGCUGGGCCUGCUCGCAGAAGACGAUGGGAGGCAGCCUGACCAGGCCCUGGUGUGGGCUGUGGACCAGAGAUGGGUGAACAGACUCACACUCACAUGGGCAGCCUUGCCUGUGCCCGGUUCCAGGGCAAGUCAUUUUGACAAAACAGGAACUUAGGGGCUGUUGAGGUGCUUUAAGCAGGAUGUGGAAGGGCAUGUGGCCCAUAUAUGCAAAGUUAAUUUUUUCAUGGGAAUUUAAAAUGCGUGUGUGUGUGUGUGUGUGUGUGUGUGUAGUGGUUGUGGGGAGCUGUGUGUGCCUGCGAUCCCAGGACAGGUGAGGCCUCACUGUGAAUGGCUCGAUUCGGUCCAUAGGUCAUGCCCCUGACCUAUAGGUCACUAAGGCACCUGUACCUGCACCGAGCUGACGCUCCCUGACUGCAGAGCCCCAUCCUGUUGGUGCCCACAGGCCUAGAUCUUGUGCUUGGCUGUGGGAUCAGAGGCUUCCUCAGGAGAGGGCACUGAGCUGUGGGCUUCGGGGAGAAGGAUGGAGAUGGGAAAGGGGGUAAAGGCGAGGACUCCUCUCCUGGGCUCUGCAGGUGGCAGCUUUGGUCACACUGACAGUCCUAAGAAUGGGUGAGACUUAACAGUCGGUGUCCCUCCUCAAGUGGGGUUCACGACUGAUCAGGCAAGUUUGCAGCAGCUGAUGGGUGAGAUGUCAUCGAGGGGCAUUCCUCUUUGGGUCUGGAGUUUUGGCUGUCAAGCUCCUGUUCUUCCAGCCAUCCAUCUCCAUGUUACGAUUGUCCUGGGACCAGAGAGACUUGAGAAGGUGGCAUGAGGCUGUAGAAAAUGUGUCUUCCUAUACACAGAGAUAUGAUGUCUGCUUUGAGUCUAUACCUGUCGAGUUGUGUCUUGGACUUACGGUCUGCCAAGGUGGUAAAUGUUAGCUGUUGAUGGGAUCAUCACUGAAGUGGAAGGCUCCACAAGGUUUACAAAAUGUGUUAAGAAGAAUGUUGAUGGUGGUGUGUGGUGCCUAACAUCUUAAUCUCAGCAUUUGGUGAGGCAGAAGUGGGAGGAUCACAUGAGGCCAGUUCAAGACCAGUCUGGGCAACAUAGCAAGACCCCCAUCUCUACAAAAAAAUUAGAAUGUUAUGAAGAUACUGAAAAGAAGAAAGGAGAAUGUAGUGGGUAAAGGUCUGGGCCCUGGAACAGACUGGGUGCAGAUCUUGGGCUGCCCAUCACACUGGUGGAGAGCAAGUUAUCUAUUACUAUUUUAGGCUCUAAUCCCACCAUACGGUGGCAAAAGUUGUGCCCAUCUCUUAAGCAUAUGUUAAAAGUUAAAUAAUAUAAUAUACGUAGAGUCCACUGUUUGACACAAUAAAAAUGAACUAUUACUGGAGUAAAAUAGUGUCCACUUCUUCAUGGCUCUUUCUGCCUUCCGCUAGGUUUGAGCGCCAGCGCCUGGCUGAGUGCCCUGCUCACCUCCUAUUAGAGCCCCCACGCUCUGUCGCCUCACCAUGCUGUGUGCUGGCCACUGCUCUGCCUCCCACACCGGACUGCAGCCUCUCAAGAACACAGGAGUUCCAUAGUUUUCUCAUGAAUGAAUGCUUUGACAAAGUGAAGAGGGUCACUUAGAAAUCACAGCUUAGGCAAAUUGUUUUACCUUUCUUCAUCUGUCUUGACGUUUAUGAAAGAGUACAGGCUGGGUGCGGUGGUUCACGCCUGUAAUCCCAGCACCUGGGGAGGCCAAGGCGGGUGGAUCACCUGAGGUCAGGAGUUUGAGACCAGCCUGGCCAAAAUGGCGAAACCCCUUCUCUACUAAAAAUACAAAAA